GGGGCACCCAACUCGUCGACUCCUGACACCGCAGCGGGGUAGGCUGCUGGACAGCCCCGAGCGCCUGCAGCUGCUGCUGCCAUCUCUGAUCUACAUGCUUCCAGCUCUGCCAGUGGCAGCCCCCCUGCUGCUCGCAGUCUGAUCAGCAACCCCUCGGGUCCUCGCAUCUUCCCUGCUGCGCGCUCCUGUCCCAGCGCGGCCGCCGAGAUUUCCGACCUUGUCCCAGGCAGGGCGGUAGCGUUCCGGAUCAGUCCUUGCCUCCGUGCCCCCACGCACAGGCAGCUCCAGGAGCAGCGGCCAGCAACCCUUCUGGGGACACCUUACUGUAGUCCGGCAGGACAGCCGAUCAGAGCCGCUCUAGGGGGUGGUCGGAGUGCCCAUUUCGGCUGGAAUCCCAACUCGGCUCCUUGCUCUGUGACCUUGGGGUAGUUAGUUGACUUCUCUGAACCUCGGGUUCCUCAUCGGUGUAAUGAGCAAAACAUAAACAAUCUUUUUCUCACAGUUGAGGUUAUCCACAGGAAGCAUUUAGGAGAACUGGCUCAGGUAGACAUCAGUAACUAUUAGCUGGAAUUCGGUUACCACUAUUGCAUUCCUUCCUAGCACUGCCAGGGGCCUGGGAAUUCCCUCUCCCAGGUAUUUCCAUAUCCUGUCAGGUAUUCCCCCACCUAUUGGAAUAGCUCUGCCUACAUGGUUCUAAUAGGACCAAGAGAUUGGCGUCAAGUCCAAGGGGCACCAUUAUUAUCUGCAUUACUUAGAUUGCAGAUGAUGACAGUAAGAUCAGGGAACAGUGUUACCCUUAGACCCACCCACAGUAUUACCAGUGCCUAUGUUGCUAUGGCUAACUUUGCUAUUUAUAACAGCAUCAUCCACAUUUCAGAUUCUAUACGAGAGGGAUCUGCAACUGCUCGGCUGGUGUCAUUGCUAAUAGUAUUAUUAGUUUUGCUUCCAAUAAAAAGGACUAUUUAUAUGAUGAUUGCAAUUACUUCUACAGGCCCUAAGGCCCUGCUUAUAUUGUGUAGGCUCAUGUUGCUCCUCAUGAAGCCGUUAAGGGGGUAGCAGAGAGCUUCCCUCCUGCUAUAGCCAAAGCUCUGGCUUCUUGUGCCUCCCUGCUGACCCUGCUGAGUGCUGGAGCUCAGUUCCUAUGGGACAGACCUUGGCUGCCGGCUGAUGGGCAUUCAGCAUGGAGGUGGUGGGUGUUGUUAGAUGUGUGUACACACGUGCAUGCCUACACACACACACACACACACACACACAGAGAGAGAGAGAGAGAGAGAGAGAGAGAGAGACCUGGUCUUAACUCUCUGGGUUGGGUCUAUGAAGACUGUGAGGGAGAUGGACAUCCCGGGUCAGACAGAAAUGAUGUGACAAGAGGAAAGUUUCCUGAACAGCUCAAGAAAUUCAAAACAAGGGCAGAGAUACAGACGCUGGAGCUGAAACAGAGAGGGGGAUGUUGUGGCGUCAAGGGAACGGACCGCAUGACUGCUGAGCUCUCAGGGUUAGAGUUGGAGAGGUGUGGCCUGCUCUGGAGGAAGAGAAGAGGAAGUGGAGAUGAGUGGUGUGUGGGAUAGAGAAGGCCACAGAACCCUGGACCCCUGGGUUCUGAGGCUGGUACCGGAUGUGGGGAAGUCUGAGUUUCCUCAGGGCUCCUAGCUGCAAUUGGGAGGCUGAGGCCCGAGACUGGAGAGACAGAGCUCUCUCAGAACUGCACGGGGCUACCCUCUUGGCCUCACUGGUCAGUGACUCCCAUUUUUGGGGUCAAGGGUAGGUUGCCCUCCAUGUUCCAGAGCAGUUAGGUCCUCAUUGGCCUUAGGCCCUCUUCCCUCACUCUCCCACUGUCAGACAGAGGUGAAAGGGUGGUCCAGGGUGUUGGCCCCAAAAUGACUCCAACUAUAUGGGUCUCUGGGCUGCCCGUCAGAGAGAUGGGAGCCAGGUCUGUGAGCAGCUCCAGCUCCAGCCCAGAGAGAAGGGAGGGAGGGCACCAGAAGGGGGCCAGGCCCAGGCCCUGGCACAGCUCAGAUGCAUGGCAAACAGUCUUCCCAGCACCCGGUGGGCACUGGCUGCUCCUGCCCAAUGGUCCCCACUCCAGCCCCAGAACAGUCCUCCCAAGCACCCCAAUGCCUGGAGCUGGUCUCCGCACCUCUAAUCUGGCCCCAUCAAGAACCUCCUCCCUCUGAAAGGUCAGAGAGAGGCCCUAAGCAUCUGGUUGUGCCACUCCUCUCCCAACUCUGACCCUAGGGAAUGAUAUCCAGACACAGUGGGGGAGAUGGGGGUUAUGAUGGCAGGGAGGUGGGAGGAUCUGGGAAAAGUAGGAAAUUUCCCAUCAUCUCAGGCUUAGGAAAGUGCAGGGACAGGUAUGAAGGCAGAUGCUGAGAGGGCAGGGAAGAUGGGGGAUAAACAGUGGGCCUGGAAUGGGAGUGCACAGCCAGUGGAAUAAACCUGAUCUCUAGGAAGUCCUGCCUGUAGUCUAACCUUCAAUUCUCUUGCUGCAUCAUUGGCCUAUUCCAUGGCAUACCUGGAUCUCCAUGCUCUUCUAAGUUUAGCCCAACCCUUAAAGAUGAUGUAGCUCUGAGUCUUCUCUCCUGGGAGCACAUUGCCCUCGUGCCUGACUUGGCUUUACUAGGGAUCCAGGGUCAGCCCUAUCCUUCUCUGAGCCUCAGUCUCCAUUUCUCAAUGUCACAACACAUCCUUUUUAUGAGAGUGUAAGUGCUUCGAGAUCUUUGGAGGAAUAUUCUGGGUUCUAGAGCUUCUGAUAGCCAGGGGUAGGAAGGGGUAGCCCCUCCCAUUUAUUCUCCCCCCCCUUAGUCCACCCUCCAGCCCAAGGCUUUCACAAAAGGUAGGGUGGGGGAAGGGAGGGGCUGGAUAGAGGCCAGACUGGCAGAGACAGGGGCUUUGUCCCAACUGAUUUCUGAGCCAAGAGUUCCGGUGGGAAAGCCCGUGCCAGGCAGAAAGGAGAGGCUGGGAAGAAGAAGGGAGGAGGCAGCCAAGGAAGGGGGAUGGAGAAUGUUGGGGAGUAAAGAGAGGAGUUUCCUUACAAAUAAUGGUGGGGAGGAAGUAGAGGAGAGGGUGGGCUCAGGAGAAGCUGUGCUUACUUGCGUUCGGUCUAGGAGGCCCUCCUGGAAAAGGCCAGCCUGCAGCAUGGCCCAGCUGUUCCUGCCCCUGCUGGCAGCCCUGGUCCUGGCCCAGGCUCCUGCAGCUUUAGCAGAUGUUCUGGAAGGAGACAGCUCAGAGGACCGCGCUUUUCGCGUGCGCAUCGCGGGCGACGCGCCACUGCAGGGCGUGCUCGGCGGCGCCCUCACCAUCCCUUGCCACGUCCACUACCUGCGGCCACCGCCGAGCCGCCGGGCUGUGCUGGGCUCUCCGCGGGUCAAGUGGACUUUCCUGUCCCGGGGCCGGGAGGCAGAGGUGCUGGUGGCGCGGGGAGUGCGCGUCAAGGUGAACGAGGCCUACCGGUUCCGCGUGGCACUGCCUGCGUACCCAGCGUCGCUCACCGACGUCUCCCUGGCGCUGAGCGAGCUGCGCCCCAACGACUCAGGUAUCUAUCGCUGUGAGGUCCAGCACGGCAUCGAUGACAGCAGCGACGCUGUGGAGGUCAAGGUCAAAGGGGUCGUCUUUCUCUACCGAGAGGGCUCUGCCCGCUAUGCUUUCUCCUUUUCUGGGGCCCAGGAGGCCUGUGCCCGCAUUGGAGCCCACAUCGCCACCCCGGAGCAGCUCUAUGCCGCCUACCUUGGGGGCUAUGAGCAAUGUGAUGCUGGCUGGCUGUCGGAUCAGACCGUGAGGUAUCCCAUCCAGACCCCACGAGAGGCCUGUUACGGAGACAUGGAUGGCUUCCCCGGGGUCCGGAACUAUGGUGUGGUGGACCCGGAUGACCUCUAUGAUGUGUACUGUUAUGCUGAAGACCUAAAUGGAGAACUGUUCCUGGGUGACCCUCCAGAGAAGCUGACAUUGGAGGAAGCACGGGCGUACUGCCAGGAGCGGGGUGCAGAGAUUGCCACCACGGGCCAACUGUAUGCAGCCUGGGAUGGUGGCCUGGACCACUGCAGCCCAGGGUGGCUAGCUGAUGGCAGUGUGCGCUACCCCAUCGUCACACCCAGCCAGCGCUGUGGUGGGGGCUUGCCUGGUGUCAAGACUCUCUUCCUCUUCCCCAACCAGACUGGCUUCCCCAAUAAGCACAGCCGCUUCAACGUCUACUGCUUCCGAGACUCGGCCCAGCCUUCUGCCAUCCCUGAGGCCUCCAACCCAGCCUCCAACCCAGCCUCUGAUGGACUAGAGGCUAUCGUCACAGUGACAGAGACCCUGGAGGAACUGCAGCUGCCUCAGGAAGCCACAGAGAGUGAAUCCCGUGGGGCCAUCUACUCCAUCCCCAUCAUGGAGGACGGAGGAGGUGGAAGCUCCACUCCAGAAGACCCAGCAGAGGCCCCUAGGACGCUCCUAGAAUUUGAAACACAAUCCAUGGUACCGCCCACGGGGUUCUCAGAAGAGGAAGGUAAGGCAUUGGAGGAAGAAGAGAAAUAUGAAGAUGAAGAAGAGAAAGAGGAGGAAGAAGAAGAGGAGGAGGUGGAGGAUGAGGCUCUGUGGGCAUGGCCCAGCGAGCUCAGCAGCCCGGGCCCUGAGGCCUCUCUCCCCACUGAGCCAGCAGCCCAGGAGGAGUCACUCUCCCAGGCGCCAGCAAGGGCAGUCCUGCAGCCUGGUGCAUCACCACUUCCUGAUGGAGAGUCAGAAGCUUCCAGGCCUCCAAGGGUCCAUGGACCACCUACUGAGACUCUGCCCACUCCCAGGGAGAGGAACCUAGCAUCCCCAUCACCUUCCACUCUGGUUGAGGCAAGAGAGGUGGGGGAGGCAACUGGUGGUCCUGAGCUAUCUGGGGUCCCUCGAGGAGAGAGCGAGGAGACAGGAAGCUCCGAGGGUGCCCCUUCCCUGCUUCCAGCCACACGGGCCCCUGAGGGUACCAGGGAGCUGGAGGCCCCCUCUGAAGAUAAUUCUGGAAGAACUGCCCCAGCAGGGACCUCAGUGCAGGCCCAGCCAGUGCUGCCCACUGACAGCGCCAGCCGAGGUGGAGUGGCCGUGGUCCCCGCAUCAGGUGACUGUGUCCCCAGCCCCUGCCACAAUGGUGGGACAUGCUUGGAGGAGGAGGAAGGGGUCCGCUGCCUAUGUCUGCCUGGCUAUGGGGGGGACCUGUGCGAUGUUGGCCUCCGCUUCUGCAACCCCGGCUGGGACGCCUUCCAGGGCGCCUGCUACAAGCACUUUUCCACACGAAGGAGCUGGGAGGAGGCAGAGACCCAGUGCCGGAUGUACGGCGCGCAUCUGGCCAGCAUCAGCACACCCGAGGAACAGGACUUCAUCAACAACCGGUACCGGGAGUACCAGUGGAUCGGACUCAACGACAGGACCAUCGAAGGCGACUUCUUGUGGUCGGAUGGCGUCCCCCUGCUCUAUGAGAACUGGAACCCUGGGCAGCCUGACAGCUACUUCCUGUCUGGAGAGAACUGCGUGGUCAUGGUGUGGCAUGAUCAGGGACAAUGGAGUGACGUGCCCUGCAACUACCACCUGUCCUACACCUGCAAGAUGGGGCUGGUGUCCUGUGGGCCGCCACCGGAGCUGCCCCUGGCUCAAGUGUUCGGCCGCCCACGGCUGCGCUAUGAGGUGGACACUGUGCUUCGCUACCGGUGCCGGGAAGGACUGGCCCAGCGCAAUCUGCCGCUGAUCCGAUGCCAAGAGAACGGUCGUUGGGAGGCCCCCCAGAUCUCCUGUGUGCCCAGAAGACCUGCCCGAGCUCUGCACCCAGAGGAGGACCCAGAAGGACGUCAGGGGAGGCUACUGGGACGCUGGAAGGCGCUGUUGAUCCCCCCUUCCAGCCCCAUGCCAGGUCCCUAGGGGGCAAGGCCUUGAACACUGCCGGCCACAGCACUGCCCUGUCACCCAAAUUUUCCCUCACACCCUGCGCUCCCGCCACCACAGGAAGUGACAACAUGACGAGGGGUGGUACUGGAGUCCAGGUGACAGUUCCUGAAGGGGCUUCUGGGAAAUACCUAGGAGGCUCCAGCCCAGCCCAGGCCCUCUCCCCCUACCCUGGGCACCAGAUCUUCCAUCAGGGCCGGAGUAAAUCCCUAAGUGCCUCAACUGCCCUCUCCCUGGCAGCCAUCUUGUCCCCUCUAUUCCUCUAGGGAGCACUGUGCCCACUCUUUCUGGGUUUUCCAAGGGAAUGGGCUUGCAGGAUGGAGUGUCUGUAAAAUCAACAGGAAAUAAAACUGUGUAUGAGCCCAGGCAA